GAUUCCAGCUCUCGCGCCCGACGAGGUGGAUUUGGCUGUCCACCGAGCUCCGGCGCCUGUCGUUCUAAUUGGGUUUGGAUUUGCACCGUUAAGGAGGGGGGAAGAGAAGGAAGAGGCGGGCGAGGAAGGCGAGUCCAGCUAGCGGCUGUUGCGGGGACCGUAGCCCCAGCUGCAGCUCCGAAGAAUCCCCCGCCACGGUUUCGGUGGAGCGUCUGGGCACGGGAUGGAGUGAAAGAGCGAGUGCCUCUCCAAGCGGGGGUGGGAGGGGGUCAGGCUGUGCAGAGGAGAGAGACAGCGAGAAGAAGCCGCGGCUGGCUACUGCGAAUUUGGGAUUCGAUUGGGAGGGACCGCUCACUCGGGGGAAAUGGAUUCUUUACCACGGCUGACCAGCGUUUUGACUUUGCUGUUCUCUGGCUUGUGGCAUUUAGGAUUAACAGCGACAAACUACAACUGUGAUGAUCCACUAGCAUCCCUGCUCUCUCCAAUGGCUUUUUCCAGUUCCUCAGACCUCACUGGCACUCACAGCCCAGCUCAACUCAACUGGAGAGUUGGAACUGGCGGUUGGUCCCCAGCAGAUUCCAAUGCUCAACAGUGGCUCCAGAUGGACCUGGGAAACAGAGUAGAGAUUACAGCAGUGGCCACGCAGGGAAGAUACGGAAGCUCUGACUGGGUGACGAGUUACAGCCUGAUGUUCAGUGACACAGGACGCAACUGGAAACAGUACAAACAAGAAGACAGCAUCUGGACCUUUGCAGGAAACAUGAAUGCUGACAGCGUGGUGCACCACAAGCUAUUGCACUCAGUGAGAGCCCGAUUUGUUCGCUUUGUGCCCCUGGAAUGGAAUCCCAGUGGGAAGAUUGGCAUGAGAGUCGAGGUCUACGGAUGUUCCUAUAAAUCAGAUGUUGCUGACUUUGAUGGCCGAAGCUCACUUCUGUACAGGUUCAAUCAGAAGUUGAUGAGUACUCUCAAAGAUGUGAUCUCCCUGAAGUUCAAGAGCAUGCAAGGAGAUGGGGUCCUGUUCCAUGGAGAAGGUCAGCGUGGAGACCACAUCACCUUGGAACUCCAGAAGGGGAGGCUCGCCCUACACCUCAAUUUGGGUGACAGCAAAGCGCGGCUCAGCAGCAGCUUGCCCUCUGCCACCCUGGGCAGCCUCCUGGAUGACCAGCACUGGCACUCGGUCCUCAUUGAGCGGGUGGGCAAGCAGGUGAACUUCACGGUGGACAAGCACACACAGCACUUCCGCACCAAGGGCGAGACGGAUGCCUUAGACAUUGACUAUGAGCUUAGUUUUGGAGGAAUUCCAGUACCAGGAAAACCUGGGACCUUUUUAAAGAAAAACUUCCAUGGAUGCAUCGAAAACCUUUACUACAAUGGAGUAAACAUAAUUGACCUGGCUAAGAGACGAAAGCAUCAGAUCUAUACUGUGGGCAAUGUCACUUUUUCCUGCUCCGAACCACAGAUUGUGCCCAUCACAUUUGUCAACUCCAGCGGCAGCUAUUUGCUGCUGCCCGGCACCCCCCAAAUUGAUGGGCUCUCAGUGAGUUUCCAGUUUCGAACAUGGAACAAGGAUGGUCUGCUUCUGUCCACAGAGCUGUCUGAGGGCUCGGGAACCCUGCUGCUGAGCCUGGAGGGUGGAAUCCUGAGACUCGUGAUUCAGAAAAUGACAGAACGCGUAGCUGAAAUCCUCACAGGCAGCAACUUGAAUGAUGGCCUGUGGCACUCGGUUAGCAUCAACGCCAGGAGGAACCGCAUCACGCUCACUCUGGAUGAUGAAGCAGCACCCCCGGCUCCAGACAGCACUUGGGUGCAGAUUUAUUCUGGAAAUAGCUACUAUUUUGGAGGGUGCCCCGACAAUCUCACCGAUUCCCAAUGUUUAAAUCCCAUUAAGGCUUUCCAAGGCUGCAUGAGGCUCAUCUUUAUUGAUAACCAGCCCAAGGACCUCAUUUCAGUUCAGCAAGGUUCCCUGGGGAAUUUUAGUGAUUUACACAUUGAUCUGUGUAGCAUCAAAGACAGGUGUUUGCCAAACUACUGUGAACAUGGAGGAAGCUGCUCCCAGUCCUGGACUACCUUCUAUUGUAACUGCAGUGACACAAGUUACACUGGUGCCACCUGCCACAACUCCAUCUACGAGCAAUCCUGCGAGGUGUACAGGCACCAGGGGAAUACAGCCGGCUUCUUCUACAUCGACUCAGAUGGCAGCGGCCCACUGGGACCUCUCCAGGUGUACUGCAAUAUCACUGAGGACAAGAUCUGGACAUCAGUGCAGCACAACAAUACAGAGCUGACCCGAGUGCGGGGCGCUAACCCUGAGAAGCCCUAUGCCAUGGCCUUGGACUACGGGGGCAGCAUGGAACAGCUGGAGGCCGUGAUCGACGGCUCUGAGCACUGUGAGCAGGAGGUGGCCUACCACUGCAGGAGGUCCCGCCUGCUCAACACGCCGGAUGGAACACCAUUUACCUGGUGGAUUGGGCGGUCCAAUGAAAGGCACCCUUACUGGGGAGGUUCCCCUCCUGGGGUCCAGCAGUGUGAGUGUGGCCUAGACGAGAGCUGCCUGGACAUUCAGCACUUUUGCAAUUGCGACGCUGACAAGGAUGAAUGGACAAAUGAUACUGGCUUUCUUUCCUUCAAAGACCACUUGCCUGUCACUCAGAUAGUUAUCACUGAUACCGACAGAUCAAACUCAGAAGCCGCUUGGAGAAUUGGUCCCUUGCGUUGCUAUGGUGACCGACGCUUCUGGAACGCCGUCUCAUUUUAUACAGAAGCCUCUUACCUCCACUUUCCUACCUUCCAUGCGGAAUUCAGUGCCGAUAUUUCCUUCUUUUUUAAAACCACAGCAUUAUCCGGAGUUUUCCUAGAAAAUCUUGGCAUUAAAGACUUCAUUCGACUCGAAAUAAGCUCUCCUUCAGAGAUCACCUUUGCCAUCGAUGUUGGGAAUGGUCCUGUGGAGCUUGUAGUCCAGUCUCCUUCUCUUCUGAAUGACAACCAAUGGCACUAUGUCCGGGCUGAGAGGAACCUCAAGGAGACCUCCCUGCAGGUGGACAACCUUCCAAGGAGCACCAGGGAGACGUCGGAGGAGGGCCAUUUUCGACUGCAGCUGAACAGCCAGUUGUUUGUAGGGGGAACGUCAUCCAGACAGAAAGGCUUCCUAGGAUGCAUUCGCUCCUUACACUUGAAUGGACAGAAAAUGGACCUGGAAGAGAGGGCAAAGGUCACAUCUGGAGUCAGGCCAGGCUGCCCCGGCCACUGCAGCAGCUACGGCAGCAUCUGCCACAACGGGGGCAAGUGUGUGGAGAAGCACAAUGGCUACCUGUGUGAUUGCACCAAUUCACCUUAUGAAGGGCCCUUUUGCAAAAAAGAGGUUUCUGCUGUUUUUGAGGCUGGCACGUCGGUUACUUACAUGUUUCAAGAACCCUAUCCUGUGACCAAGAAUAUAAGCCUCUCAUCCUCAGCUAUUUACACAGAUUCAGCUCCAUCCAAGGAAAACAUUGCACUUAGCUUUGUGACAACCCAGGCACCCAGUCUUUUGCUCUUUAUCAAUUCUUCUUCUCAGGACUUCGUGGUUGUUCUGCUCUGCAAGAAUGGAAGCUUACAGGUUCGCUAUCACCUAAACAAGGAAGAAACCCAUGUAUUCACCAUUGAUGCAGAUAACUUUGCUAACAGAAGGAUGCACCACUUGAAGAUUAACCGAGAGGGAAGAGAGCUUACCAUUCAGAUGGACCAGCAACUUCGACUCAGUUAUAACUUCUCUCCGGAAGUAGAGUUCAGGGUUAUAAGGUCACUCACCUUGGGCAAAGUCACAGAGAAUCUUGGUUUGGAUUCUGAAGUUGCUAAAGCAAAUGCCAUGGGUUUUGCUGGAUGCAUGUCUUCCGUCCAGUACAACCACAUAGCACCACUGAAGGCUGCCCUGCGCCAUGCCACUGUCGCGCCUGUGACUGUCCAUGGGACCUUGACGGAAUCCAGCUGUGGCUUCAUGGUGGACUCAGAUGUGAAUGCAGUGACCACGGUGCAUUCUUCAUCAGAUCCUUUUGGGAAGACAGAUGAGCGGGAACCACUCACAAAUGCUGUUCGAAGUGAUUCGGCAGUCAUCGGAGGGGUGAUAGCAGUGGUGAUAUUCAUCAUCUUCUGUAUCAUCGGCAUCAUGACCCGGUUCCUCUACCAGCACAAGCAGUCACAUCGUACGAGCCAGAUGAAGGAGAAGGAAUAUCCAGAAAAUUUGGACAGUUCCUUCAGAAAUGAAAUUGACUUGCAAAACACAGUGAGCGAGUGUAAACGGGAAUAUUUCAUCUGAGAAACUGCAGGGUUCCUACUACUCUUUUUUCUUGUUGUUCAAUUAUCUCCUCCCCCUCUUCUCUCCUGUCUUUUGAUUUGGUCAUUCUCUUUAUUUUCUGCUUGCCAUGUCUUUUCUGGAACAUACUUGCAUCCACCACAGCAUCAAUUCCCUUGAUCCAGCCCAAGAGACCAGGCAGCCAUGGCCACUGCCUUCCUCUCUGAUGAACCUAUCGGGUGAAAACGACCACUCAAGAGACUGACUUCGCCAUUCAAGACAAGGAAGAGACACAUGUGUGCACUCCUGCAUGUUCAGUUCUGUACUUCCAGUUUCUAAAAUGCACUGUUCAGUUUUCCAACCACUUGGUGGUUCAGGCUUGCUUUGAACCUGAGCUCUUAGGCACAUGACGGUCAUUCCUGACAUCCUCCCCAGCUCAAGUCUAUUCUUACCAUAGAACCCAGGGCAGGGAGAGAAGAACCUAGAGGCCUGGUUUGCUUUGGUGGCAUUGUAAAAAGAGUAAGAGAGGUUUGGUUUGUGGUGGUUUGCUUUCUUUACCAUAAGCAAUCCCUUGCCUUAACUCAUCACCCUUUUUCACUAUGACCCUUAGACCCUGAGUAUUUUCAAAUAUAUGAUUGCUGAUAGUAGUGACCAAAACUACUUUGUUCCUUUCUUACCACUCUCUCCUGGGGCCGACACGUUGGGACAGCACACCAUAGCAUAAAGCUAGGGGAUGCAUGGAAAUAGCAGCUUGAAACUAGGAGGUAACAAGAAAGCUUCUAGGAAGUAGAUGUUCCAUAUCUUCAAAAUGCCUCCUCCAAUUUUGUAAGAAUGCUAGCUAGGUAUUCCUGGGAUUAUUAUACUGAGAUAUAUAUAUAUACACACACACACACAUAUGUGUAUAUAUGUAUAUAUAUAUGUGAGUAUAUAUACACACACACACACACACACACAUAUAUAUAUAUACACACACGCACACAUAUAUGUUGCUGCAGCAUAAAGAAAUUGAAAUAAAAGUUUAAAAUAGUACCCGGUUCAAUGAAAGAGCCUAAACCAUCUUAACUCAGCUUUAAAACAAAAAUUAAAUCAGGAAAAAAUGAAAAAAAAACUGCAUGAAAGAAGAAAAAUACCAAACAGAAUUCUUCCCUUCCAUUCACUCACUAAAGACCUGGUGAAGAUAGUUAAUUCAAAUUUGCAAGUUUCACAUUUUUUAACAUCAAGCUAUUCUCCAAGAAGUUUAGGAUGCAUUAACAUAAGUGAAAUGGUCACCUCUAGCUAACUAGCAUUGCUUGAUUUCAGAGGAGCCCUUAGGUUCUGUAGCAUACCACAUUUUCAAAUCUGCUAUACCCUAUAUACAUAAAGACCCUUCCAAACAUCUUUUUAUAGGCUUAAACUCCCAAAAGAGGUGGUGACAAAUUUCAGGGUCUUUGUCCCUUUUGGUAACAAAGCAUUGAAAACAGUCAUUCCUUCAAGAAGGCACCUUGAGCUCAUCCAUGGGGUGGCGGUAAAGAUCUUAAUGAUUUUUCUGUGGCAAUAUGCAUCAUUCUUUGUCCUGGGCCAUCUUGGAGAAAAAGGUAAGGAGAAGACAAUGUAAAUGCUCCAAGAUAGUGGAAAUGCUCAUGUAAUGAUUCUUAGGUGUGGAAAAUACUUGCUGAUUCUCUUUAUGAGGCAGAUUCAAUUUAGAAAACAAUGACCACAGCUCUAUUUGCCAUCCUUGACAGUUAGCAGACAUUCCAACUUGUGCUUAGGGUACACUGUCUCUCGCCUCUCACAAUGAGGAACUUAGUUGCUUCAUUCCAUUUCAAACACAGCUUUUCUUUCAGUUUCAGAGCUUAUGAGUUAAGGAUUUAGUUUGCAAUCAUAUUUCUCUAUUUUAAGAUGUUGUUUCAAAUGCAUAUUCUCUCCUCGAAAUUUUCUGUGGAUUUGAGCUCAAUCGCUUUAUCAUCUACAUGAUAUCUUUUGGCUAGUACAUUUAUUUUAAAGUGAUUUUAACCAUGAUAUCAUUUCUCUCCUUUUAGUUUUAAUAAGAUGAAUGAUUCUUUAGUAAGAUGAAGGAUCUUUAAACACUGUUUUCCCCUGCCCUUUCCUCCCUUUCUUCAAUUUUCAUUUUUGAAUUUUCUAUUUCCAUAAAAAGGCUAUAUAAAUCAGCCUUUUGCUUGGCUAUAUAUUCCUUUGUCCCCUGAAAUAAAAGUCACCAUGAAGUGUAGUAGGUUUAGCCUGAAGCAGCUCCAAUAAUGAAAUAGAAAGGCAAAGGAAGGUAUGAGUAAUAAAGCUGGAACUCUUCAUUAUUCAAUCUUUGAGCAGUGAGGACUAUGUUUUGCUGACAUAGUGCUAAUAGAAGAAAUGGAGACUAGCAAAGGCUAACUCAGAGUAUUUGAUUUUCUCAUCUAAGUAUAUAUGCUUGUAGAUUGUCCUGUAGGAUGAAGAAUCUGUGAAGCUCUAUCCUGACCACAAUGGCACUACAAAAUCAACUGGCAUCUUCCUCACGUGUGUAGACUCCAUGCACACUACAUACCACAGACCUAAAUGUAGAUGCCAGGACAGUGCCGUCUACACGUCACUCCUAUAAGUAGUCUCAGGGCUAAAGCAGAAUUAUUUUUACAGGGUUGAAUUAUUUCAUAACCCCAGAGAACACUAACUUUCACUAGAUAUAUAUGAAAUGCAAGUGAUCCGUACCCUCCAAAGUAGAAUGUAAUUUACAAUUAGAAAUCGUGCUAACUCUGACUGUCUUUCCUCAGUGGUACCAAGAUCUAUGUAGUUUUAUGUAAUUGUUCAAUUGUGUGAGUGUUUUAAUCCUUCUGCAAUUAUCAUCUCGAAGGAGACUUUGAAAGCAUCUUAAUCUCUCUUUAACCAUUUUUUUUUUCUUUUUCCUACCACAUUCAGGUUUCCCAACUACAUGCUCUGGCCAACUGGGCCACCAUGAUCUCUUCCACUUAAAUCCUCAGCCUUCAAUAACUGCUGUUUACAAAAAGAUCUUAUGGAAUAUGGAUCACUUUACAGUAAAGCCAAAAGUACUUGUGAAAUUUCACAUUUUAAUGGAGCUGUUUCAUUGAUAUUUUUUUCCACCAAACAAAUCUAUUUAUGUAAGCAACAGUAUAUUUGCUUACUCUAAAAUAUAUUUAUCCUACUGCAUCAUUUAUUGCAUAUAUAGCCUCAAUUGCCAUCUUUAUGAAAAUUUGUCUGGAGAAAUAGACAUUUGUCAUUUCUAUAGACAUAUUUUUAUGACUAACUUUGCCUCUUCUAUUUACCCUCUGCUGUAUGCAGAAGAUUUUAAGGAUCCUAGCGGUGAUGUUUUAAAACAACUUUUUUCCUCUCCUUAGUAAUAACAGAGAUGGUAUUAACUUGACUUCUACCUUUUGUCAGACUCAUCUCCACCAACGGGUAGCAAGAGCAGGAUAGAACAAAAUAAAGAGAUUGUUUUUCUUUUUUCAUUCAUGAAGUAUUUAUGGAAUGCCAAUGAGUGCCGGGCUAGGCAUUGGGUGAACAUAUAUAAAUUACACCUUGUUUUUGCCCUUGGGGAGCUCAAAGUCUAGCUGGCAAGGCAUGUAUUGUUGCAACAGGGCCACACAUAAAGUGUCCUAGAAUGCAGCACAAGGUCCCGCACAAUUAUUUUUGUGAAGCAUCUGCCAGACUGAAAGAAAUGUAAAUUUCUGGGAAAUAUCUGUUAUUUUUUAAAUUACUGCUUCCACCUUCUGUAAGCUGUUUUGUUUCUCCUCCUCAAAGUAGAUAUCUAUCAAUGCAUAUAGAUUUCUGUAGAAAGGGGUGGAUUGACUUUUAGGAACAGUAAGAAUAGAUGGUCUCUGUCUCUGCCAUACAUUUGAGGAGGCUGAAUUCUCUACAUUCUUGUUUCGGGUCAGGUUGGGGGAUUCCAAAAGUCUUGCCUCCCAUGAGUUGGACCUAAGAGUGUCCACUUUGGCCCCUCUCCUUCCCUUUUCUCAGUUCUUCCACAGCCAUGUGUUUAUGACCUAUUGCAUGCCGUUGUUCUUCCAGAUGUUCCUGAAGGUGGUUUGGUUGUCAUCCAGCUCUUCCUAAAACCCUCCUUAGUCCUGAUGAGCCAUUUUGACUCUACAUAACAUUUCUGAACCUAACUGAAGUCUACCCUUCCAUCAGUAAUUGACUAAAAAAAUGUUGUCCAUUUAUGUGAGGUCUCACCUCUGAGCCUGAGUGAGUGUUUCCUGUCUUGAAGGUCAUACUUGCUCCCUCUCUGCAGGAAGUUAAUUCAGUUAGAAGAGUUGCACUGGGAGGGUGCAAGCACAGCCAACUUAUCCAGUCCAAGAUAUCCAGGGAGAUGAGGAUGAGACCUGUUGAAUUUUUUCUUAGGAAAGGAAAGGUCUUGACAGACUGUUCACCAACUGCCCUAGCUUCCUUUAAGCUUCCCCAUAGCUACCAUCCAUCAAAACCUCAUUGCAGCUGUAGCCUACCAAAAGGCCUUUGGGAUACCUGUAUGGUUCUGCCAGUCAUUCUUCCUUAAUGAAAAGGCUUGGACAUACUUAGUCCUCAAUUAUCCUACAGGUCAUGUAUCGACUAAAUAAAUAAACUGACUUCAUUGUUUCUGAAGAUGGCAAAGGCGAUUAAUGGAAGAAGAUGCAGACAAACUCAAAACUUUCAGAAGUCUAGGAGGAUAACUGAGUGCUAUUUUCUGUCUCAUGCAGUUUGAACAUGUUUUCUUUAAAAUACACAUAAUGUAAUUGAAUUAUUUCUAUAUACUGUUCUUGAGUCUUUCUUGACCUCUUCUUUUAUCCCCUCUUUCAUAGUCUUGUUUGUGGAACCAUCUACUCUGCAGAUUUUUAUUGUCUCUAAUUAUCAGCUCUGCCUUCACAAAUUCCAAAUUUGAACCACCUAAAGGGGAAAAAAUGCAACACACACACGCACGCUCACAUGCACACUUUGUACAAAUAGGGCUGUUAUUCAACUUUUCUCUUGAACAUUCUACAUACAUAUCUGUUUGGUAGGGAGAGAAGCAUUCCUCUUUUAUGUUGACAAUUAUUUGAAUCCUUCAUAUAAGGUUUUAAUAAUUAACCGGUUUGCUAUUUUUCAGUGAUUAUUUUAUCUUAUUUUGCACUAAGGUACUCUGAGGAAGAACAGAAAAGCACAUUUUCUAGUGAAAUAUUGUACUUUGUAAGCUAGAUGUCUGUCUUAUGUAAUGUUUAUAGUCUACAAAAUGGCUGAGCAGACAUGAACAAAGGUUAAUGCAAAAGUUGGUUUUGGUUUCAACCACACCUGCUGCGAACUUGACGAGGAGGAAGAGGGGCCAGUGGCAGUAAUUGGUGGCCAUCUGAGGUGAGGAAGGAAAUUGCUUCCACCAUGAAUCAGUGGUGGCAGCCUUUCCACUUUCAUGGCUCCUCACUCAGGAGUCUCUUUAGUGCAUUUGGAUCAUUGUCUUACUCAUUAGGGAAAGAGGCAAUAUCAUGGGCUUUGCAUGAAUAAUUCUUUACUCACAUUUGCAUGAUUUUUUUUACCUUCCAACACUUCUUCAGUCACAUUCUUUUUUUUCAAUUUUUAAAUUUUUUUUCAGGAUUUUCUCAGAGUGCUUUAGAACUAUUAUUAUAAUUAUCUAACCUGCCCAGGUUAAGCACCCAGAUGCAACUUUCAGGAAAUGAAACUGUCAGAAAACUGCCCUAGGUCUAUUAUCAAUCAGAGCCCCUGUGAGUGGAAGUCCUCAGAUUCUGGAAUCCAUCCAGUGUCUUUCUUUUCCUUCCAUUCAUCCUGACAUGAAUAAGCAUAACAUAACUGUAAGAAGGAGUGUAGUGUCCCAGCCCUGACAACGAGUACCGCCAGGGACCUACCAUCUAACACCAUCUGGGAACACUAUUUUUUCUCAGUCCUUCCAGUUGACACAAGGAAACCCUUUAUAAAAUAGGACAAAAUUAGGAGAUUAGUCCCAAGCCAAGACCAAAGGUGAAGAUAAUUGUGUUAGUGAUUAACGCCUGGUCUUAUUUUAACGAGUGUCAUAGUCUUACAUGCUUCAGAUGCCAGAAAUAUCUUCAGAGAACGUGAACAAAGUGCUGGAUAUGAAACAGGAAUAAUGCAUUCCUCUACAGACUCUUUGAAAGGCUUUCUCUUUCAAGAAACCUUGAAGGGAAAAUAUUAACGGGCAUCAGCCUGGGCAUACUUUCCCAUCAGAGUCAGCCUCUAUCACAAACAUUUUACAUGAAAUAUUCACCUAGUCUAUUCUCUUUGAAAGGUAGUAUCAACCUGUGUAACCUUGUCCUGCCUUAAAUACUGUUGCAAAAAAUACCAAACUUUGCUUAAAGCAGCAUAGUUACAUUGAGAAAGAGACUGCCUUUAGUGAGGACAAAGACCAAGAAUUUUCUCUUUCUGAAUCUGGCAGUUGACAGGCCUCCUGAUAUCCUGUGUUGCCUUGGACUAACAUUUUCCUUAGUCACUAGCCUAGGGCAGAAAGGCAGCCAUGUAUAAAUGAAUACCCAUGGCCAUGUUCCAAUAUAACUUUAUUUACAAAAUCUAAUUUAGUUCAUAGGUUACGGUUUGCUGAUUCCUAAGAUAGAGCAUUACAGUGUCUGUUUCAGAUGGGAAGUAAGUCUUCCUAUGGCAUGUUCAGGCCCUCCUUUUCAGGGAAUGAGAAAGAGUGGGGAGGGUAUUUCAACAAGUAAUAAAUUGCAGAAUACCCUCCCCACAAAAAUACACAUAUGUCAGACUCUUUAUUAUGGUAAAAGCACAAAACAGGUCAUCUUUUUGUGGAAAUGCUGGAGUCUACCUUUUCCUUUUUAUCUUCUGAUUUUUGUUCCUAAAAUAAAAUCCCAAGUGAUGUUGCCUCAUUCCAAGUCAGUUUUGUAGACCAUGUAACAUGUCUUAAUACACUGUAUGGGGAAAAAAUAAAAGUUAGCCUUAGAUUUCUUUGUUUUCUAUGGUUAUUGUUGUACAGAAGAAAGACAAACUGUAAAUAAUGUAUAUUUAAUAAAGAGAACAUUUUGUAUGAUUUUGUGUGGAAGACAAA